GCGCCAUUCCAAACAUGGCGGCUCCACUAGGGGGUAUGUUUUCUGGGCAGCCACCCGGUCCCCCUCAGGCCCCGCCGGGCCUUCCGGGCCAAGCUUCGCUUCUUCAGGCAGCUCCAGGCGCUCCUAGACCUUCCAGCAGUACUUUGGUGGACGAGUUGGAGUCAUCUUUCGAGGCUUGCUUUGCAUCUCUGGUGAGUCAGGACUAUGUCAAUGGCACCGAUCAGGAAGAAAUUCGAACCGGUGUUGAUCAGUGUAUCCAGAAGUUUCUGGAUAUUGCAAGACAGACAGAAUGUUUUUUCUUACAAAAAAGAUUGCAGUUAUCUGUCCAGAAACCAGAGCAAGUUAUCAAAGAGGAUGUGUCAGAACUAAGGAAUGAAUUACAGCGGAAAGAUGCACUAGUCCAGAAGCACUUGACAAAGCUGAGGCAUUGGCAGCAGGUGCUGGAGGACAUCAACGUGCAGCACAAAAAGCCCGCCGACAUCCCUCAGGGCUCCUUGGCCUACCUGGAGCAGGCAUCUGCCAACAUCCCUGCACCUCUGAAGCCAACGUGAGCAAAGGGCAGAGGCAGUUGGCCUAUGAGUGGGCUGAUGCGUGAGGUUGGCCACACAUUCCUUCCUGUGGACUUGACAUUUUGGAAGAACUCUUUGCCAGAUAAUGAGUUCAUUUUAGUUUUAUGCUCCCAUUGAAAAAUUUUCCACUAUUUUUAUAAGCUGUUAAUUUCUUGAGUACUUUAUAACAUGUCUGUAGCUUGGAUAAACCAAGUAAGUAUUUUUUUUUUGUCUUUAGCAAAGUUUAGACUGUGAAUAUGAUGACACAGAUUCUUUUUUAUGGUGGCUUUGCUUGUUUUAAAUUUUUGCAUGACUUUUCAUCUUUUUAUGUGUGUUUCCUGUAGUUUGAUCCGAAGGAAAAGAGUAUAGUAGCCUGAGAAUCAGGAGAUGGGAGUUUUAGUCGUAGGCCUUAUGAUAAUUACCCCGCGGUGGUGUGUAGAAAAGUAUGUAAAUUUGCUCUGUUUUAAGACUUUGAACUACCUCAAGAAGAGGAAUCUAAUACAAUAUUUGUAAUGUUUCCAGAGCUCUCAGAAUGAGGAUUUUUUUGUAAAUAGGUCAGAAGACGAUGGAACUGUCCUGGGUUAGUAUAGUAAUCUUACAGUAGGAUCCUUAGGUUGAUGCUGACUUCUGUUUGGGGUAUGUUUAUAUUUUAUGUGGUGUUUACUUUUUUUUUUUGACAUAGAAGGAUAUAGUGGGAGCAGUGAUACGCUAACAUUCAUUACAUUCUGCAGUAAUGAAUCUGUUUAAUGGGUCAGUCACUGUUUUCAGUAGCAUGACAGUGGGGUCAUAGGUGAGCUGUGAGGGGCUAAAUCUUGCUCUGAUUGUCUCUUUCUGUUUUGAGUUUUGUUUGCGUGUAUCAUUUUUGUUCUACAUUUUGGGAGGGGAAACAUUUUCCGUUAAGGAAGGUUGUUGCCAGUGGAUUUGACUCCAAGGGACUAGAGUGUCGUGGUGGGGGUGGGGAGGGGCUGCAGGGUGAUCAUUGGCUACUGAGCCUCCACAGAGAGCAUGUGGUGCCCUGCCUUUGGGAGGGUAUUUUGCUCUCGUUAGUUUUGUGGGCAGCCUCAGAUUCCCUGUUGAGUUGCUGUUAAGAAAUGGAGAUUUCUGGCUCUCAUUGGGUAAGGUUUUCUGAGUUUUAUAUCUUAUUAGAUCACAUCCCUUUACCCAGAACAAAUGCUUCACUGUCUUCUGAUUGGCAGUACUCCUGUGGCUUUGUGCCUUGACUCAUUUUGUUGUCUUCAGCCUUGAAGGCCCCUUCCCACAUGGACUGACAUCCACUCAUGUGCCUGAUCCCUGAAGCCUCCCAGCACCCAUUCAGUUGCAUCCCCAGGGCACAGGACUUUGAUCUCUUCUGUUGCCCUCGCUAGGUUCUCCCUGGUGGGUUAGUGCUUUGUAUCUGUCUCUCUGCCCCUCACUAAUUCUACACCCAUGAGAAUUAGACAUUAUUCUCCUUAAAUAUAUAAGGACCAUAUAAUCUGUAUCUUUUUGGUGUGUGUAUAUGGUAUCUGGCACAUGGAUCUCUGAUUACCAGCCUGACAUCAACAAAUCCCCUCAGUUACAACGUAUAGGUUAAACAAAGCUUUUAAAAGCUCAUGUGGUAUGACCUCAAGGUUGCUAACCUGGUCACUCAUGGUAAUUAGAAACUCUGAUUGGCAGCUUUGUAUUUCUUGACUAAAAACCUAAAUAAACUGAUUAGGUUUUAGGCGUUCUUUCAAAGAGGUUCUUGAGAAGAUUGAGAACUAUCCUAUUUGGUGCUUAGUGAAAAGAUUUUGAAUUACUGUACGUACCAGUUGUUGCCAUUUCUUUAUUAAAUUCAGAAGUUUUUUUGCCAAAUAACAAUUUUUCAAUCUUCUCUGUUUGUAGACAUCUUACUGGGUGAUGAAUAAUCCUCUAAGAAACCCUCUGAGCUGCUAACUUUUUCAGGGAGAAAAUCACAAGCCAUCUUCUCAAGUUCCCCUAGAAACCUGUGGAAUGCCCUCUGCCAAGCACUGCUCUGGUACUGGGGAGUGGAGUAUUAUGUCUUGGAAGAGACUCCUGCUGUGAUUGUCCAGGGGUACGUUCUGGUCUGGCUUGGUGCUUGACCUUAGGUCUGCCCACAGGCUUCAGGCUUUCAACUUUGAAACAAACAUCUGUGCCACACACAUUUUGUAAAUGAUCCCAUUCAGUCUUCUAGAAGCCUUAUAACAGAAUCAAUAUUGUUUUUCCCAUUUUCACAGAUGGAUAAUAAAUCUGUAAAAUAGGGAUAAGACUAGGACCUAUUCCCCAGGAUUACUUCUGCAGAUUAAAGGAGAUGUUGAGGCCAGGUGCAGUGGCUCACGCCUGUAAUCCCAGCACUUUGGGGGGCUGAGGCAGGAGAAUCGCUUGAACCUGGGAGGCAGAGGUUGUGAUGAGCCAAGAUCGUGCCAUUGCACUCCAUCCUGGGCUACAAGAGUGAAACUCCGUCUCAAAAAAGAAAAAGGAGAUGUUGAAUGGGAAGUCAGCAAGGGUGCUAGAAUGUAGCAAGUAUUCUUCAGGUGUUAGUGAUUUCUGUUGUUCGGGAAGAGGAGGGUUAUGGAGGAAGAGUAUGGGAUUUAGGUGGGUUAAGUGAUUUGCCCAAAGUCAAGAGGUUAGUCUUUAACCUUUGGCAGAAGCAGGAUUUGAAGUGAGUUUUCACACCCCUCUUCCCUGGUCAGUGUGUUGAUAACAGCCCACCCACCUGUGGUUCCAGGGUGUUCUUAAGAAGCCAAGGUUGUCUUGGGUGUGGUAGCUCUUUGAAAGGUAGAAAGUUCCACCAAGAAGGCCUUUUUUCUUGAAUACUGCUUAGCUUCCUUGUCAGGCUCCAAGAUGCAGAUUGCCUGUGGGCUAUCUCUCUCCACAGAUAAACCUACUCACAUCUUCAGGACAGCCUUUUUUUUUUGAGACAGGAGUCUUGCUCUGUUGCCCAGGCUGUAGUGCAGUGGCACAACGGGGUCCCACAGGCAAGUGCUGGGGAAAGGCCCACCCAGCCAUCAGGUAGCCUGUGUGUUCUACAAACAGCAGCUGGCAGCACUGUCUCCUGCCGGACAUUCCUGCCACCCGACAUCAAAGCUGGUGGGUGACCUUUUCAGCCAUUUGACAUUCCUCCCAGAAGAACCUCUGCCUCCCAGAGGUUUAAGCAGUUCUCCUGCCUCAGCCUCCCAAGUAGCUGGGCUAUUUUUUUUUUUUUUUUUUUGAGAUGGAGUCUUGCUCUGUCGCCCGGUUAGAGUGCAGUGGUGCAAUCUCGGCUCACUGCAACCUCUGCCUCCCGGGUUCAAGUAAUUUUCCUACGUCAGCCUCCCGAGUAGCUGUCAGGUGCACACCACUACACCCAGAUAAUUUUGUAUUUUUAGUAGAGAUGGGGUUUCACCAUGUUGGUCAGGAUGGUCUCAAUCUGACCUCGUGAUCCGCCUGCCUCUGCCUCCCAAAGGGCUGGGAUUACAGGCAUGAGCCACCGCGCCCAGCCUUAAUUUUUGUAUUUUUAAUGGAGAUGGGGUUUUGCCAUGUUGGCCAGGCUGGUCUUGAACUCCUGACCUCAAGUGAUCUGUCCGCCUCAGCCUCCCAAAGUACUGAGAUUACAGGCAUGAGCCACCGUGCCCAGCCCAUCUUCAUCUUCUUUACUUGAACUUAAUUCUUUUUCAUGCAUCUUCCCUUCUUUCCUCUUUUCUCCUCCACCCAAAUGUCUUAACUGUUAACAUUCCCAGGUGUUUGGUCCUGGGCCUCUGGAGGUUGUGAAGGAGCACUGCUCAGUCCUCCCUUCAAGAAAGCAGCUUCAAGGAGUUCAAUUACAAAAGCUCCUGGCAUUGGGGACCUGCCGCCAUGUUCCUGCCCAGGGCAUGCUGGUCCUGGCUGUCACCAAGCACAGUGGAGGUCAGGUGCUAGGCCAUUUCUGCCCGACACAGGCCUCCUCUAAUGAGCAGUCUGAGGCCAGGCACAGGAGGCUGAGGCAGGAGAAUCGCUUGAACCCAGGAGGUGGACGUUGCAGUGAGCCGAGAUCGAGCCACUGCACUCCAGCCUGGGUGACAGAGUAAGACUUCGUCUCAAAAAAUAAAAAAUAAAAAAAUACUGAGCAGUCUGCUUGGGCGCUUCCAUCAGCCUGGCCAUGACAUCUUUGGAGCUGUCCUGCCCUCUUUUGCCCCGGUGUUCCUUGGCCCACCUGUCAGACCUACAUCAUAGGCUCUUCCUGUCUUCUGUUUCCUCUCCCCUUUCUCUAACAUAGGUGUUUCUCCUGAGAAAGAAAAAAACCACCUGUCCCUGACAUUCAGAAGCUGACAACACUGUUCGGUCAUGCCAUUCUCCUGUUGGACAUAAACAGUCUCUGAAUGCCAACCCCAAAGUUGCUCUCAGGCCAUGAUAAAAUAAACCACUUAAUAAUUUUGUCUAAGCACGUACAAAGAAAAUUCAAGGUCAGUUUACCACUCACAAAAUACCAAACAUCCUUCUGCUGGUUAAAACGAGUGACAGCUGCCGUGUGUGUGUGUGUGUGUGUGUGUGUGUGUGUGUGUAUGUGUAUAUGCGUAUAUAUGUGUAUGUAUGUGUGUAUAUAUAUAUGUGUGUGUGUAUAUAUAUAUAUGCAAUUAUACCUUUAUCCCUACUCUAGUCCACCUUCCUAUAAAUAAGAUGUAUUGAGAUGCUCAGUGCCCCCAUUCUGACAGCAUCCAAUCGAGUGAAUCCUCACUUCCUUGAAAUCACCCAACCAGGGCCAGAAUCCUAAAAGAGGUUCUUUGUGACACCCUCUGUCUGAGAAGUCCUAUGGUUCUCUGUGAUGAAUAGACCCAACUUGUUCAAAUACAGGCAUUUCUGGUGGGCUUUGGCUGAAGGCAUUCACACCCCCCAGUGAAUGUCUUGCACUUCUAAUUGUGUCUCGGGGCAUGCCUGGUGGAGGACCUGACUGAGACAAUUGUGACUGGAUGUGGUCUGAGAGCAGGCAGUAGGAUGAGGCUUGGGGACUGGCUCACUCACUGCCCAACUGGUAGCAAAACCCAUCUGGAGCAGCGUGUGAGGUAUGGACACUCACUCACACGAGGGGGUGGCCCAGUUGCUGAGGAUUCCACCAGUGGUACCCUGGGAAAAUAUCCCUGUGGAGGGGAAUGGGAGGAGUCAAACUGUGGAAGAUAAGAGGAGUACUGCACACAAGGACAGUAGAGUGUCUGUUCCCUGCAGAGGGAUAGUGAGGAACUGAUGAGGUGACUGUGAGUGCCCGGGGCCUCUGUCGUUAUCUUGGAGGAUCACUUUGAGGUCAGGAGUUCAUGACCAGCCUGGCCAACAUGGUGAAACCCUGUCUCUACUAAAAAUACAUUAAUUAGCAUGGUGGCGGGUGCCUGUAGUCCCAGCUACUCGGGAGGCUGAGGCAGGAGAAUCGCUUGAACCCGGGAGGCCGAGGUUGCAGUGAGCUGAGAUGGCGCCACUGCACCCCAGCUUGGGUGACAGAGCAAGACUCCGUCUCAAAAACAAACACACAGUACUGCAUCCUGGGGGUGGAGGUGAGGUGACGGUAGAGAUCAGUGCUACCCUUGGAAAUCUGACAGAUACAGUAAGAUGGUCCCUAUCAUAGUUCCAUUUAAUUUGCCAGCCUCAUCUGCAGAAUCCAGAUGGAUCCUGGAGAAAAAUUAACCAAGUAGCCUCAAUCACAAAUGUUGGGUUGGAUAUUACAUCAGUGUUAGAGCAGUUAAGGGCUCAGGUAUGUGGUGUGCAGCCAUUGACUGGGUGAAUCCAUUUUUACCUACCCCAAUUACAAAACAGUUUGCUUUCAUGUGGAACAGAUAGUAUUCCUUUCAGUUUUGCUGCAGGAACAUAUUAACUCUUCCACCCCUGUCAUAAUACAGCCUGAAGAGAUUUACCAUUAAAUACUGUUUUUUUCUCUCUCUUAACUUAAUCCCGAAUUGGAUAAUUUCUCUUCAUCUUCACUGUCACCUCUACGCCAUCACUGUCAUCUCUAGACCGCUCUGCUGUUGAGAGAUUGAUGGAAUCAUUAUGCAAACUAAAAUAGAAUGUUUUAUCUAUCAAAUUGUAUUUCUUUGUCAAUAGUGUUAGGGCACAGUAGGUUCAUUUACUGCUGGUAAGGGUGUAAAUUGUUAGAAACUUUCUGAAUGGCAGUUUGGUAAUAACAAACAAAAAGCUUAAGUUUGUGUCCUUAAAUGCCUUACUUCAAUACCCAAGGCAUAUGGCCUCAAUAAAAAAUUAUGGAAGCAUGCAAAGAUUUUGUUAACAAAGAUAUAAUCAUUGCAGGGUAGAAUUUAGAAAUUUAAGACUGAAAGAUCUUUUCAGUCACCUGCAGCAAGAAAGGAGUCAAAACCUAUGUACGAUCUCAACUAGUAAAAUUUUCUCCUUGCCCAGGGAUCAUGCUGAGUUUAAGGACAGAAAUGCAAAGUGCAGCCUGGGAAAGUGUUUCAACACACAAAAAUAGAACCACCUGUAUGUAGUCUUUUUGAAAGCACAAAAUAAAGAGCAGUCCUACAGGGUUCACUGCUAUGUCCUGAAUGUUGAUGUCCCUUCCAAAAUUCAUAUGUUGGAACCUAAUGUCAAUGUAAUAGUAUUAAGAGGUGGGGCUUUUGGGAAGCAAUGGAGUCAUGAGGGCUUCACCCUCAUGAGUAGGAUAAGUACCCUUACAAAAGAGGCUCAGGGAGGCGCUCUUGCCUCUUCCACCAUGUAAGGACACGUAGCAGGCACCCAUUUCUGAAGAAUGGGCCCUCCCCAGACUCCAUAUCUGCUGGUGCCUUGAUCUUGGACUUAGCCUCUAGGACUGUGAGUGACAUAUUUCUAUUGUUUAUAAAUUAUCCAGUAUAAGUAAGAUAUUUUGUUAGAGCAGCCUGAACGAACUAAGACACUCUAAGCGGGAAACUCACAAAAAAUAUUUGGUAGUGAAAAACAGUAUGGUGUGUUAAUGUAUGGUGACAAGUGUUUGUUUGCAUUUAAAAAUGCAUUGGAGCCUCGUUUUGAUUAGGCAGUAAAUUUACCUUUAAUACGUAAGUUUGACAGUUAUAUGUAAUCAGCUUUUUUUUUUUUAAGAUGGUGUGAUUGAGGUUAAUGUGAACUGAACUUUCUAUUUCUAAGCUGUCUUCAUCUAAUUUUACCUUUCUGUGGAAAAUCAAUACAAGUCAACCAUUUUUAUUGCCCAGUUAUUCAAAGUUUUAUUCAAAGAGCAAAGAUUUGACAAUGCAUAGAAUUAACAUUGGUUUGUGGGCCACCUUCUGGGCCAGCACCAAAGACUGAAAAAAUAUUUUGCCCCCUAAAAGUUGUUAUUGAGUCUUGUCAAAUCACAUUGCUCUGUCAGAAGGUAAGACAAAUCAGUGUGGACUGAGAGCAAGGUCAGCACCGUGAACAGCCAUUGCGGUUCCUUUAACCCACUGGGAAUUCAUGCAGUGAAGAAGCAACACACCAUGAGGCAAAUGGCUCAAACCCAAAGACCAGAGGUUCAGGGGAUAUAUAUAUAUAUUUUUUUAAUCUGUAGAGAUGGGAUCUCACUAUCUUGCCCAGGCUGGUCUCGAACUCUUGGGCUCAUGCUGUCCUACCUCAGACUUCCAAGUAGCUGGGUUUUCUUUGGGCUAAUUAUUUUUUUGUAGAGAUGGAGGUCUCGCUGUGUUGCCCAGGCUGGUCUCAAAUUCCUGGCCUCAAGCUCUCCUCCCAUCUCAGCCUCCCAAAGUGUUGGGAUUACAGGCAUGAGCCAUGUGCCCAGUCUAGAAGAUCUUUGACUUCAAAGAACAGAUAAUCUAGAGACCUUCACAAGUGAUCAUGUUGGCACUAUGGUCAUUACACUGAGACCUAUAACUGGGCUAGGAUUGGUUAUUUACAGAAAAACCUUGUGGUACUUAAUUCCAAUUCAUGUUAAUUUAUGUUAUCUUGCUUAAUCCUUGCAAAGCCCUUUUAGAGGUGGGUGUUAUCCCAUCUAUAAUCUGCUGCUUGUCUUAGACCAAGGAAGUGAAAGUAUUCAGUCCAAGCAUGCUACCAUCCAUUUCUGGUAGGUUUGGUUUGUUUUUAGUUGGCUUUCCUGUUUAACUGUUAUUUGUCUUCCUAUUGAGGUUAGAUGUGCAUUUUGGAAUUGCAUCAUUUUACAUAGAAACAGCUUUCCAGUGGAGUUGACUAGCAUCCUAAGGACAAGUACAACCACUUUUGAAAUAGAUCAUGGAAAUCACAAAGUCUGAUGUUCCACAAAAUGGAGUAUGAUGUUAUGGACACUAGAAAUACAAGGUAUGGGUCAUUAGUAACGCUAAUAACAUUUUCCUAUAGAUGACUUUUAAUAACACUGGUUUAAUGUCAAUUUUUUUUUUUUUUUUUUUUUUUUUUUUUUUUUUUUUUUUUUUUGGAGACAGGGUCUCCCUCUGUCACCCAGGCUGGUUGGAAUGCAGGAGUUCGAACUUGGCUCACUGCAACCUCUGCCUCCUAGGUUCAAGUGAUCCUCCCGCCUCAGUCCCCCAAGUACCUGGGACCACAGGCACACGCCACCAUGCCUGGCUAAUUUUUGUAUAUUUUGUAGAGAUGGGGUUUCACCAUAUUGGCCAGGCUGGUCUCAAAUUCCUGGACUCAAGCAGUCCAUCUGCCUCAGCCUCCCAAAGUGAUGGGAUUACAGGCGUGAGCUGCUGUGCCUGGCAGAACAGUAUGAAGUGUUAACGCCAAAAUUUGUUUUAGCUAUCAUAUAUAAAUCAUAAGCAUAUUAUUUGGUUGGUUGGUGUUAGUUCAUUCCUUCAAUCGGAUGAUUUAAAAUAAAUGUUUUUCAAGUAUCCUCUGUGAUGUAUCCCAAAGGUUAGCUUAGAAAGAAAAGUACUUGGUGAACCAUUCCUGGUGCGGAGAGCCCUGUUUCUGCUGGACUUCUUUGGCUUGGGCCGUUUCACCAUCUGGGGUCCUAAAAGCAAAAAAAGGUUUUUUUAUAUGGUUUUGAAAACUAUGCAAGAAGCAGCUUAAUACCCACCAUCUUUUCAGGGAAAGAUAACUGCUUGUUUACUCUUCAAAAACACCCAAAUGGGACUGGCCAACAUUAGUAGUGGGAAACAAAUUGUAAAGGAUGGGGCUGGGGAGGGAGUACCUAAUCCUCAUUUGGAAAACAGAAGGUUCACCAUUGUUUGGUUCUCCAUUGUUCCUUUGAGACUUAGUGGUUGUAGCUCUAAUAAUGCAGGAUUAACCAAACCUACAGAUCAAGAGACUUUGUUUUUAUUUUUUGUGACAGAGUCUCCCUCUGUCACCCAGGCUGGAGUGCAGUGGCAUGAUCUCGGCUCACUGCAACCUCCAGCCUCCUGCGUUCAAGCGAUCAUUGUGCCUCAGCCUCCCGGGGAGCUGGAAUUACAGGCGCAUACCACCACACCUGGCUAAUUUUUGUAUUUUUUGUAGAGAUGGGUUUCACCAUGUUGCCCAGGCUGGUCUCGAACUCCUGACCUUAGGUGAUCCACCCACCUCCAUCUCCCAAAGUGCUGGGAUUACAGGCGUGAGCCACCAAGCCCGGCCCGAUUAAGAGACUUUAGAAUUCCAAGGUGAUAGAGUAAAUCUUGAGGAAUAAUGUUAGUAAUAAUACUGAAACUAUAUUGAAGAUUUUUGUGCCAAGUCCUGUGCUAAGCACAUCCUAUGGAUUAAUUCCUUUAGUCUCACGUCAGUCUGAUGAGAUAGGUGCUGUAUUAUCUUAAUUUUAAAGGCAAGGUAUAUGGAGACCUGGAGAGGUCAAGUGACCUGUCCAAGGCCACAGAGCUAAGAAUGAGGAAGACUGUAAUUUGAAUUCAGACCUCCAGGCCAGAUGGAGUCCACCUUUUGUAUAACCCAUGCUGAAGUUUUCAGGUAAGUGAUUCAGUGUCCCUUGUCUAAUCAUCCAUGAAAAAAGGCCUUCUGGAAUUUGGUACCAGGUGCUAGAAAGAAUCCUACUUCCCCUCUUAUCUACAGGGAAAUAGAAUAAGGGCCCCUGUCCCCAACAUCCCCCAAACCUUGUGGCAGUUUUUGCAUCUGUAGACUGGUUGGGUUUGUAGGUCCGGCCACAGCUGGGGCUUGGGUCCAAGCUGGGUGAUGUAGUUAUUGGAGGGGCAUUAAUCCUGGAACUCAGAUCGCCACUCAGAAAGUUCUUUGCAUAGGAGGCGAGGUUCGGCACGCUGACCACGCGGCUGGGCACGUCCUCCACCUUCUUUUUCUGUUUGUAUUAAUGGACAGGUUAGUGCAAUGCAAUGCAAAAAACAAAAUAAAGCAUUAUUGUAAAAGCAAAUAAUGCUCACCCAAUCAAAAUUGUAUCGGAGAAGAAGCAACAAUUUCAUUUAUACACUUACAUGCUAUUUUUUAAAGCACUUUUCCCUCCAAUCUUCAUUUUGUAUUAUAAAUAAAUAUGUAUGUUCACAACCUCUUAACCAAAA